GUCUGAAGGCCGAGGCCAAGAUGGCGGUGCUGUCAGCUCCUGGCCUGCGCGGCUUCCGGAUCCUUGGUCUGCGCUCCAGCGUGGGCCCGGCUGUGCAGGCACGAGGUGUCCAUCAGAGCGUGGCCACCGAUGGCCCAAGCAGCACCCAGCCUGCCCUGCCAAAGGCCAGAGCCGUGGCUCCCAAACCCAGCAGCCGGGGCGAGUAUGUGGUGGCCAAGCUGGAUGACCUCGUCAACUGGGCCCGCCGGAGUUCUCUGUGGCCCAUGACCUUCGGCCUGGCCUGCUGCGCCGUGGAGAUGAUGCACAUGGCAGCACCCCGCUACGACAUGGACCGCUUUGGCGUGGUCUUCCGCGCCAGCCCGCGCCAGUCCGACGUCAUGAUCGUGGCCGGCACACUCACCAACAAGAUGGCCCCAGCGCUUCGCAAGGUCUACGACCAGAUGCCGGAGCCGCGCUACGUGGUCUCCAUGGGGAGCUGCGCCAACGGAGGAGGCUACUACCACUAUUCCUACUCGGUGGUGAGGGGCUGCGACCGCAUCGUGCCCGUGGACAUCUACAUCCCAGACUGAGCUCCUCCCUCCCUGGGGACCGCGCUCCUCCCUCCCUGCGGACUGUGCUCCCUGUCUGGGGACUGCGCUCCUCCCUCCUUGGGGACCGUGCUCCUCCCUCCCUCCCUGCGGACCGCGCUCCUCCCUCCCUGGGGACCGCGCUCCUCCCUCCCUGCGGACCGCGCUCGGCCCUCCCUGGGGACCGCGCCCCUCCCUCCCAGCGGACCGCGCUCCUCCCUCCCUGGGGACCUCGCUCCUCCCUCCCUCCCUGCGGACUGUGCUGCUCCCUCCCUGCGGACUGUGCUUCUCCCUCCCUUGGAGCAGCCUGGACUUGCCAGAGCUCUGCCAGGUGGGGCCUGGCCGCCCUUUCCCAGGCCCUGCAGUGGCCUUGUCCUUUCUCACCUGUUUCCACUCCUGCUGUCCCCGUUGGGCCCUGGGCUUCGUCCUCUUGCUCAAGCCCUUUGUUCUGAACCUGCGUGGCAGCCGGGACUGGGGGAUCCCCAGCAAAGAGCUCUGGCUUGGGGCUCAGAAAGAGGGUCAUCGGGUCCUCGUGGGAUGCCCGGGCUCUGGGCCACCUCCCCUCCCUCCGCCCAGCCUCCCUGCCUCCAUCUCCGUCCAGGGCAGCCCCGGGCCCUGCUCCCCACUGCUAAGUGUGUCUGCUGAGCGCUGGCCCCCAUUGAGUCCUGAGGGCUGGGGCCGGGGGCCGGGUUAGUGAGGUCAGCGUCUUGUCCGAGAGGUCCCUGUGACAGCCCGGGAUGAGCCACGGGUGGAGGGCAGUGGGGCCUUGCCCAGGGGAGGACCCCACUCUUCCUGCAGGGACCUCCCCUGCGCCGGCUCCCAGUCCCUGGCACUGCGCCCACCCAGGGCUGUCAGCCUCCACCUUCAGAGGCCGGCCCGGGAAACCCUUCCAAAGCCGAGCCGGCUGCGCUGUGCACGCGGUCACGCGGGCUCCGGCUGCGGGAAGCGAGACUGAGGCAAGGUCCCUGCAGGCUGCCCACCUACGGCCGAGGCCCUGCUCUACGGCAUCCUGCAGCUGCAGAGGAAGAUCAAGCGGGAGCGGAGGCUGCAGAUCUGGUACCGCAGGUAGCGCCGCCGCCGCCGCCGCCGGAGCCUGUCGCCGUCCUGUCCCCAGCCUGCUUGUGUCCCGUGAGGUUGUCAAUAAACCUGCCCUCGGGCUGCCGCC